ACUGCGCUCCAGGACCCAGCGCAGGCGGCAGGCGGGCAGGCAGGCGGCGGCCUCGGAGGGGAGACUGAGCGGUGGCGGCAGCCAGCGGCAGGGAGGCAGGCCCAGCCGGGGACUGGAGCCGGGGACUGGAGCCGGCUCCUCACAGGGGACCAGGAGUGUGUCGCCAGGCCCUCCCACUGAGGCCCAGCACCGGGAGCCCCUGGGACACCCCACCCUCCUCCGCCUUUCUCUUCCACCUGCUCCUCUCCAUCCUCCUCUCCCUCCUCCCUAUCUCUCCACCUCAUUUGCCCCCUUCUUGGCCUCUCCGGGUCUCCCAGCUCUCCAUCCUCCCCAGCUCUCCACUCCCGGGCUCUCCCCGCCCCCAGCAUGCUUUUCCCGUGGGGGCUGAGGGCUUGAGGACUCCGGGCCCUUGCCUCAACCAGGGCAGGGCCCAGGCUCCAGGGGGGAGGGGGAAAGGGGGCGGCCCCCUCCCCCAGCAGGCCCUCCCCUCCCCCACUUCUCCUGAUGGCCGGCUUCCUUUUCUCCACCCAGUCCUCGCCCCCUGUGGCCCCCCCAGGCCGGCCCGGCUAGGGGAGGGGGCGGGGGCCCUUUCCUGGGCCAGCUUCCCCCUCCCCCGGCUUUGCCUGUGCCCCCCCCUUCCGUUUUCACCUUCCUCUCCUCCUUUCCUCCCUCCUUCCCCUCCAUUUGCUCCUUCCCCCUCUCCUCUCUCCCCUUCUCUCCUCCAUUUUCUCCUUUCCCCUUCCUCCCCUCCCCGGCCCGCCCUCUCCUCUUCCACCUGUCCUUCCUCCCUGCUCCUGUGGAGCCACCGUUUUGGAUUAGUUGGGAGCCACCACCGGCGGCGGGGGAGGGGGCCCUGUGGACUGCCCUCUCCCCCCGCCCAGCCCCACCACCACCCAGCGCCAGAGCACCUCCCGCUGUCGGUCUUCGGGCCUCGAGGGAGCCCAGCCCUCCGUCCCACCAGGAUCCGUGGCGAGUGGGGGCCGCGGCAGCUGCGUCCCCAUGAGGAGGGGAGGAAGAUGCCGGCUGAGCUGCUGCUGCUGCUGAUUGUUGCCUUCGCCAGCCCCAGCUGCCAGGUGCUCUCAUCACUGCGCAUGGCUGCAAUCCUGGAUGAUCAGACAGUGUGUGGCCGCGGUGAGCGUCUGGCCUUGGCCUUGGCCCGGGAGCAGAUCAACGGGAUCAUCGAGGUCCCAGCCAAGGCCCGAGUGGAAGUAGACAUCUUUGAGCUGCAGCGGGACAGCCAGUACGAGACCACGGACACCAUGUGUCAGAUCUUACCCAAAGGGGUUGUGUCUGUCCUUGGGCCCUCCUCUAGCCCAGCAUCUGCCUCCACCGUGAGCCAUAUCUGUGGAGAGAAGGAGAUCCCCCACAUCAAGGUGGGUCCCGAGGAGACACCCCGCCUUCAGUACCUUCGCUUCGCGUCUGUCAGCCUGUACCCCAGUAACGAGGACGUCAGCUUGGCGGUCUCCCGAAUCCUCAAGUCCUUCAACUACCCCUCGGCCAGCCUCAUCUGCGCCAAGGCUGAGUGCCUGCUGCGAUUGGAGGAACUGGUGCGUGGCUUCCUCAUCUCCAAGGAGACGCUGUCAGUGAGGAUGUUGGACGACAGCCGGGACCCCACACCACUGCUCAAGGAGAUCCGUGAUGACAAGGUGUCCACCAUCAUCAUCGACGCCAACGCCUCCAUCUCCCACCUCAUCCUCCGUAAGGCCUCGGAACUGGGAAUGACCUCAGCGUUUUACAAGUACAUCCUCACCACCAUGGACUUCCCCAUCCUGCAUCUGGACGGUAUUGUGGAGGACUCCUCCAACAUCCUGGGCUUCUCCAUGUUCAACACGUCCCACCCCUUCUACCCUGAGUUUGUCCGCAGCCUCAACAUGUCCUGGAGGGAGAACUGUGAAGCCAGCACCUACCUGGGCCCUGCGCUGUCAGCCGCCCUGAUGUUUGACGCCGUGCACGUGGUGGUGAGCGCUGUCCGAGAGCUGAACCGCAGCCAGGAGAUCGGUGUGAAGCCUCUGGCCUGUACAUCGGCCAACAUUUGGCCCCACGGGACCAGCCUCAUGAACUACCUGCGCAUGGUAGAGUAUGAUGGGCUGACCGGGCGGGUCGAGUUCAACAGCAAAGGGCAGAGAACCAACUACACCCUGCGCAUCCUAGAAAAGUCCCGGCAGGGCCACCGUGAGAUUGGGGUGUGGUACUCUAACCGCACCCUGGCCAUGAAUGCCACCACCCUGGACAUCAACCUGUCGCAGACACUGGCCAACAAGACCCUGGUGGUCACAACCAUCCUGGAGAACCCAUACGUCAUGCGCCGGCCCAACUUCCAGGCCCUGUCGGGGAACGAACGCUUCGAGGGCUUCUGCGUGGACAUGCUGCGGGAGCUGGCCGAGCUGCUGCGCUUCCGCUACCGCCUGCGGUUGGUGGAGGAUGGGCUGUACGGGGCGCCCGAGCCCAACGGCUCCUGGACGGGCAUGGUUGGCGAGCUCAUCAACCGGAAGGCAGACCUGGCUGUGGCCGCCUUCACCAUCACAGCUGAGCGGGAGAAGGUCAUCGACUUUUCCAAGCCCUUUAUGACCCUGGGGAUCAGCAUCCUCUACCGAGUGCACAUGGGCCGCAAGCCUGGCUACUUCUCCUUCCUGGACCCCUUCUCCCCUGCUGUGUGGCUCUUCAUGCUUCUUGCCUACCUGGCUGUCAGCUGCGUCCUGUUUCUGGCUGCCAGGCUGAGCCCCUAUGAGUGGUAUAACCCACACCCAUGCCUGCGGGCACGCCCCCACAUCCUGGAGAACCAGUACACGCUGGGCAACAGCCUGUGGUUUCCCGUGGGGGGCUUCAUGCAGCAGGGCUCGGAGAUCAUGCCCCGGGCGCUGUCCACGCGCUGUGUCAGCGGAGUCUGGUGGGCCUUCACCUUGAUCAUCAUCUCCUCCUACACGGCCAACCUGGCCGCCUUCCUCACCGUGCAGCGCAUGGAGGUGCCUGUGGAGUCGGCCGAUGACCUGGCAGAUCAGACCAACAUCGAGUAUGGCACCAUCCACGCCGGCUCCACCAUGACCUUCUUCCAGAAUUCACGGUACCAAACGUACCAGCGCAUGUGGAACUACAUGCAGUCGAAGCAGCCCAGCGUGUUCGUCAAGAGCACAGAAGAGGGCAUUGCCCGCGUCCUCAACUCCCGCUACGCCUUCCUGCUCGAGUCCACCAUGAACGAAUACCACCGGCGCCUCAACUGCAACCUCACCCAGAUCGGGGGACUCCUCGACACCAAGGGCUACGGCAUUGGCAUGCCGCUGGGCUCCCCGUUCCGGGAUGAGAUCACACUGGCCAUCCUGCAGCUUCAGGAGAACAACCGGCUGGAGAUCCUGAAGCGCAAGUGGUGGGAGGGGGGCCGGUGCCCCAAGGAGGAGGACCAUCGAGCUAAAGGUUUGGGCAUGGAGAACAUUGGUGGCAUUUUUAUCGUGCUCAUCUGUGGCCUCAUCAUUGCUGUCUUCGUGGCGGUCAUGGAAUUCAUAUGGUCCACACGGAGGUCAGCUGAGUCCGAGGAGGUGUCGGUGUGCCAGGAGAUGCUGCAGGAGCUGCGCCACGCCGUUUCUUGCCGCAAGACGUCGCGUUCCCGCCGGCGCCGACGCCCGGGCGGCCCGAGCCGGGCCCUGCUGUCACUGCGCGCGGUCCGCGAGAUGCGCCUCAGCAACGGCAAGCUCUACUCGGCCGGCGCGGGCGGGGAUGCGGGCAGCGCGCACGGGGGCCCGCAGCGCCUCCUGGACGACCCGGGGCCCCCCAGCGGAGCCCGACCCGCCGCCCCCACCCCCUGCACCCACGUGCGCGUCUGCCAGGAGUGCCGGCGCAUCCAGGCGCUGCGGGCCUCGGGGGCCGGCGCGCCUCCGCGUGGCCUGGGCGUCCCCGCCGAAGCCACCAGCCCGCCCCGGCCGCGGCCUGGCCCCGCCGGCCCCCGGGAGCUGGCGGAGCACGAGUGACCACGGGCGGGGCUGUGCGGGCGCCCGGACUGACCGAAGGGACGGGGCCCGCCCCAGGCCCCAGCAGUCUCCGCUCCCGCAGCGGGCGCGGGACAGGACUUGUGCGCCGGCGCCCCGGACGCCGCGAUUUUGCCUUUGGUUCCCCGCGAAGUCCGAGGCCUGGCUCUGGAGCCCGCCUGCGCCCCCCAGUGGACUCGCGAGAGGGUGCCGCGGGCGAGAAGGGCGCAGGAACCGAGGACUCCAGGGGCUGGGGACUUCGGGGGCGGCUCUGGGAAGCGGAAAGCAGUCAGCGGAGAGGACCCCAUUCUGGGACUGCUCAGGCUCCCCAAGACUUGACGCAGCCCCCCACGCUUCUGGAGGUGGGGAGGGCCUCUGGACAGAUGGGUGUCCCCUGGUGCCCCUCCACUCUUCUCUUCCUCUCUUUUUUGGGGGGAGAAACCUCGGAAUUUCUAUGAGACCUCCCCCAGGGAGGGGGUCAGUUGGGCCCCCAUCCCUCCCCUUGCCACAUCGCAGCCCCUGUUGGAAUAAAAAAAAGAACAAAACCCCA